ACCGGUGUAUCAUGGGAGCGGCCCGGGCUACACGUUAAAAACACUAAGGGGAGCGCGCGAAGCUGAACUUGGCGCUCGAUGGGGGCCGUUAGCCGCCCUAGAGCGCGCGGAGCCGCAGAGGCGUAGCUGGACUACAACGCAGUGCAUCUCGGGAGGCCAACUCGACUGGACUGGCCCCCUCAUGCCCGGCUGCGAGCUGCCCGUGGGCACCUGCCCGGACAUGUGCCCGGCCGCCGAGCGCGCCCAGCGCGAAAGGGAGCACCGCCUGCACCGCUUGGAGGUGGUGCCGGGUUGCCGCCAGGACCCGCCCCGCGCGGAUCCGCAGCGCGCGGUGAAGGAGUACAGCCGACCCGCCGCCGGCAAGCCCCGGCCCCCGCCCAGCCAGUUGCGUCCGCCCUCCGUGCUGCUGGCCACCGUGCGCUACCUGGCCGGUGAGGUGGCGGAGAGCGCCGACAUCGCCCGCGCCGAGGUGGCCAGCUUCGUGGCAGACCGCUUGCGAGCUGUGCUCCUGGACCUGGCGCUGCAGGGAGCGGGCGACGCCGAGGCAGCUGUGGUGCUGGAGGCGGCGCUGGCCACGCUGCUGACCGUAGUGGCGCGGCUCGGGCCCGACGCGGCGCGGGGACCCGCGGACCCGGUGCUGCUGCAGGCCCAGGUGCAGGAGGGCUUCGGCUCGCUGCGGCGCUGCUACGCGCGGGGCGCCGGGCCGCACCCCCGCCAACCCGCCUUCCAGGGCCUCUUUCUGCUCUAUAACCUGGAGAUGGGAUCUCGCAUGUUGCCACUCGAAUUCCUGGGCUCAAGUGAUCCUCCUGCCCCACCCUCCCAAGUAGCCGGGUGUGGCCAUCAUGCCCAGUGAAUGGUUUAUUUUUGUCCACACUGUUCCUCUGAAGAAGGCAUGGCUCGGUGGAAGCCCUGCAUGAGGUUCUACAGCUGCCUGCUGCCCUGCGCGCCUGCCCGCCCCUCCGCAAGGCCUUGGCGGUAGAUGCUGCCUUCCGAGAGGGCAAUGCUGCCCGCCUGUUCCGUCUGCUCCAGACCCUGCCCUACCUGCCAAGUUGCGCUGUGCAGUGCCAUGUGGGCCAUGCCCGCCGGGAAGCCCUGGCCCGCUUCGCUCGUGCCUUUAGCACCCCCAAGGGCCAGACCUUGCCUCUGGGCUUCAUGGUCAACCUCUUGGCCCUGGAUGGACUCAGGGAAGCACGGGACCUGUGCCAGGCCCACGGGCUGCCCUUGGACGGAGAGGAGAGAGUUGUGUUCCUGAGGGGUCGCUACGUGGAGGAAGGGCUACCGCCUGCCAGUACGUGCAAGGUGUUAGUGGAGAGCAAACUUCGAGGACGUACCCUGGAGGAGGUGGUCAUGGCAGAGGAGGAAGAUGAGGGCACGGACAGACCUGGGUCCCCAGCCUGAGGAGGGAGCGUGAGCCUCCCAGAGCCCCAGGACUGGGCCAGAGCACUUAGGUUUCUUUUUCCAUGGUUUCCAGGUAAUAAAAGGAACUUGUUUUGUUGGUA